AUAUUUCUCCUUCUUCCCCCUUAGAGCUCAGCUUCUUGUUCUGGGAAAGCCCUGGAGAGACCUACGCCUACAUGACGUUUGCUUUUGAACUCCCUUGACACUUUCAGAGGCUGGUAGCAGAAACCCAUCUUAAACCAGCUGAGGCGUCCCAGGGAUCUUGCUUGCUCAUGGACCCCAAAGGAGAUCAAGAAGGCCUGAGUGAGGGGUGUGGCUUUACAGUGAAGAAAAGUAAUUGCCUUCCUAAGUUAGGGACCCACUGACUUAGCUGGGUUCAGGUGCCUACUGCAGAACCCUUAUUCCCCACCUGUGUCUUUGGGUGAAAGGAUCAUAAGAUGGCAUGACAGCUGCUACAAAACAGGGGGCAGAAUAGCUCCCAGGAAAAAGGAGGAGUGCUUGUCAAAUUCUUUGACAAUAGGAAGGAACGUUUAUUGAGCAUUUGCAUUUUCCAGGCACAUUUGUAGCUGCUUACCUGUGCUCUUUCAAUCCUCACAACAGCCCCCACAAAGUAAGUGCAGCUAAAGGAAAAUGAAAAGGGGAUUUGGUUACGCUGUAGUGUGGUUGGGAUGACAAAUAUGAGAUGGUAUUUAUAAGUCGCUGGGGGUGAUGCCCAGCAGGUAGUACUUACGCCGUGGUAACUUCUGUUUCCAUCUCUUAAAAAUGCUUUCAAUUAUUUUUAUUUCUAUCAGAGGAAUACAUACAUAUAUUCAAGCCCAAAGUCAUAUAGGAAGGCAGGUUAAAAAUGAAAAGCCACAGCCCCUUCCCCAGAGGCAGUCUCGUUCUUUCUGUCCUUAGAACUCCUGGUGGUUCUCCUGCAUCUCUAAAUCAUGCGCUCGUGGCGCUGUCUCUUGAUGAAUCAACUUUAGGCACUUCUAUUGAUUUUCUGUUUUAUCUUAUCUCCCUUAUGGUUUACGUCCUCUUUUCUUCUUCUCUCUCUCCCAUAACCCAGCUCACCCGCUACUCUGCUCCUUCUUUUUCUUUAAUCUCCAUUACUUUUCUUUCUCCUGUUUUUUUUCAGUCUCUUUCCUCACACACAGCCAAUCACUGUGUGGCCCACGCACAGGUACCCCUCCACCACCUCUUCCCCACCUUCUUCCUUUUCUUCUUUCUUGCAGUGUCUUCUCCACAUCUGUGUCCUAGAAACCUUUACUGUCUGCCUGUGGUUUUCUCUGGUACCUUUAUCUUGACCCUUGUCUGCCCAUUCUGCCCUGCUUUAGGGUUAUUUCUAGCUGUGUUACCACCACUUGUUAAAAAUCUUGUUCUUGCAUUCAUUACCUUAUGAAGCCUGCAGAACACGCCACGAUGUAAGUCUUUGGAUUCUCAUUUUGGGGAUAUGAAAACAGAGCAUCCUAAGAUGGACUCAGAGUCCCAGGGGGAGAGGGAAAGAGCCACAUGCAUAGCUUAUUUGGGGACCAAGUCUGAUGUGACUCACCCUGGGUUCCCAGAAGGGGCUCAGGAAAUGUUUGUUGUGGGAUUGAACAGGAAGCUACCCUAAUGGUAAUGAGAUGAAUUGGACAUUCCUCUCUGACUUCUAUCGUUUGAUUUUCUGAGGCCAUUCACAUACACACAUACAUGCUGUCUCACACACCACUCACGUGCUUCUGGCUUUAAAUUCGUCUCCUCCUACAUCUUUUUUAUUGUUUUCUAUUAAGCCUGAUUUCUGUUUGGGAGGCAGCCUGCUUGUAACAAGCCUUUGGUAGUUUUGUCCUCCCGUCGCCUGGGAUAAUUUAUGGGCUUGGAGAAAGGGAACUUGCCUCCUGUACUGUCAAUAUUAAAUAUACAUUGCUUCCCUCACAAAAUAGCAUUCAGAGUUGUAAUAAAUCCUCUGGAAAUUACCUGGAGUUAACUAUGAGUUGGUUAAGUGCCAGUAAUUAGCAUUGCCUGGGAAUUUUUGCUGACACAUAGACUCAUCCUGGUUGCCUUGCUUGGCUUUAAUUGUAUCCCGGAGCUCUAGAAUUUUGGACCUGGAAGAGGUCUUCCCAGUCUAGCUCUGCUUUUCAGCUUAAAGGACGAAGAACCUGAACCCAGGGAAGGAGGGAGUUUGCUUAAGGACACACAGAUUCCCAGCAGCCAAGGAGAGCAGAGUCCGGGUCUCCCAAGCUCAUGUUUUCAGCCCCUUUGAUCUGUUCAUUUCCAGGCAGGGUGCUCUCAGGUCAAGCUAAUGUGUGGCAUGAUGCAGUUUGCCAAGCUGUUUUGCACAGUCUUUCCAAAAUUAGUUAUUAAUUGGGUGCUAAUCUUGUUGGCCACCACGAAGGCAUUGUCUUUAGAGUAGCUUAAGGUUGGUGGAUCCAGGCUGAGGCAUGUUGUGGAAGCCACUGCAGGGCCGUUAGCAAUAAACAUGUACCAGGAGGUCAUCUGGUUCUUUUUCUGCUUGGAGAGGCAAACAGUAACCCAGCUUAUCCCUUCUGGGCUCCCAUCUGAUAAAGACCUCAGCCUUUGAAUAGACACAGAUGAUUAAAUACAGUUCAGCUCUGCAAAUGCCCAUGGAGCACACUACUCUGUGCCCAGCAUUGUGCAAGGUAUCCCGGGCAUAUGGGCAUGUAAGAUGGACUUCUUGCUUGGAAAAUUAUAAAGUGUUUAAUAGGCAGACAGAUAGGGAUGUAGAGAAACAGCUGAGUUCUAGCCUCAGAAACAGAGACUUGAGAUGAAACCAAGGGUUUACUAACCGUAUGACCUAGCCCAGUUCUGUAACCUUGGUGAGUCUUGAUUUUCUCAUCUGUGAAAUGGGGUAGUUGUGAGACUUGAAUAGGAUUCUGUAUGGGAAAUGCCUGACACAUAGUAAGAGCUCAGUAAAUGAUAUUAAUAAUAAUGAUUUUUUGUGUGUUUUUUUGGGGUGGGUGGGUGGGGCUAAUCACAGAAGAACUAAGGGUGCCCAAAGGAGGGAAAAUUAAUUUGAUUUGGAGGAUUGGGGAAGAUGUCUUCAUGGCUUUACUGCUUAUUAGAGUCGUUUUUUUAUUUCUUCUUAACUUGAUCUUAGUGCCUCAGUUGAGUAAUAUCAUUCAUUCAUUCACUUGAUUUCCCUUAAAAAUAUUUAUGUUGGGGAUGGGGCAGGUGCAUGGGGGAAAUAAAUGCAAGCUAAUGUGUCCCUGCCCACAGUGAACGCAGAGUCUGGAGGAGAGAGGCGGGAAAGCCACGUGGCUGUGCUGCCCUGGGCCAUGGAGACCUGCCUUGCCUUUCCUCCUCCUCACCUUUGCUCACAGCUGCCUCUCCUUCUCCUGAUCUGGGGCCUGACCCUCUUCCUUUCUGAAAGGCCAGCUCUUUGCUUCCCCAUGAAGUGACAGUGACAGGAAUGUGACAAUGUAAUGCCACAAUUAAGAGCAUUUGGGACUUGGCUCCAAAUGUCAGUCCACCCCUUUUCAUGACACCAGUUGGUCCUUUUGCCUUUCUGAGCCUUAGGUUUUUGUGUCUAUAAAACAGGCAUAGAAUUGUGAGAAUUACAAGGUGAUAUUGAUCGGGUGCAGAGCAUGUUACCUGGAAACACCCUGAAGGCUUUAGCCCAUAUUACUACCCUGAAAUCCAAGUCUCCUUAUACUUUCUCACCAACUAAUUUUGUUCUAAGAAUAAAGCUCAAUGUUUCUAGGUUCCUUUGUAAUUUACAAAGCACUCUGCUUUGUCGAAUCCUCAUAAUCAGGUGAAGUGAGCAGGAAUUAUUAUUCUCUUUAUUUUAUAUAAAAGGAACAGGCUUGGAGAUGCUGAUUGAUGUGACAGAGUCCCAUGCCUGAUUCAGUCAAAGUCCAAUGCCACCAAAUCCCACGCUCUCUGCAAUCUGCCAUCCUGCAGCUCAGUUGGCGGAGCAGCACUGACCUGUGGUCAGCUGUGUCACACUGUGCAUCUGUCUCAUACCACAUUCCCCGUAGCAUUCUGUAGAGCUAUGCUUAUUUUAACAUGCUCAGUUUGCACAACUCUAUGAAGUAGGCUUGAUUAUUUAUUCCUUUAUUUUUACAAGAAGGAAGUGGAGGCACAGAAAAGUUACAUGAUUUUCCUAAGUUCAGUCCCAGCUGCUGGGCUGCAAAGCACCAGCUCCUGUCCUCCACACCAUGCUGUCUUUUUAUUAUGAGUUUGUGCCUCAUUAUUUGGAAUAAAAUCCUUGAUUCAACGAUAUUCAGUGUAGACCCUUCACACGGGGCAGGACAGAUGACCCCAGUUGUAGCACGAAGGCACAGAAUCAGAACUCAAAGUGCAGAAACAGAGCUUAAUGCCAGGAACCAGUUGGUGGCUGGGUGAGGAGGGCAGGAGGGAGCACACAGGAGACAGGUGCAAAAGGAUUAGAGGGGCAUGAGCUAAAUCACAUGAGAUAAAUGGGCUCAGCAACCCACCCACGUCCUCUGAGCACUCACACCCCUUGGGAAAUAGGGGUUGAUGGAGUGGUAGCAUCCUUUCUGUGUAUUGCCAGAGGUGGACCCUGGAACCAGACUGCUGGGUUCAACUCCCAGCUCCAUAACUUGCCAGUUGUGUCACUGUGGGCAAGUUUCUGAACCUCUCGGUACCUCUUGGGUUUCUGAUAAGAAGAAAAGGGGGCAAUGAACUGUGCUUGUCCAAGGGGCUUGGUAAGAGGAUUAAAUCACUUAUUAUUUAUAAAGUGCUGAGAACAAUGCUUGGCCCUUAGCUGUGUGAAAGUAGUUGUUGAGUAAAUAAGACAAAUGGGGGGGUAAAGAGUGUCAGAGGGCUGGGUGACCUGACCAGGGUCAUAGUGGGUACUGGAACGGGACCUGAACUCAGGGCUCCUGGAACUCACCCCGUAGAAAUCUACACUGUUUGCCUUAUAUUUCACUACUGGCUGCAAAAUUAAGAAAAUGAAACAAAAUGCAACAAAAAACAUCUACCCCAGUAGUUCUCAGUGGUUUGGAGAUGAGAUGAAGCUUUUCGAAAUAAGCAUCCAAAUCAGCCUUGUGUAUCUGUGCUGGGGAGGGGUGUGUUUGGAGGAGUGAGGUAGGAGUGUGGGUAGUGGGGGAUGAUGGAUUUUUAACAAAGCCCUUUUCUCCAUGUAUCUUUUGAGAACUCUGGCUGUCACUUGUCUCUGACACGUGGACAUCUCCAUCCAGGCCCCUUUUUAAAACCUUUUGAUUCUCAUUAAUGCUGGUUUUCAAUUAAAUUAUUCUUAGCCCUAGAAACUACCCAAUUAAAGAAGCAAUUUUCUGUACUUUCCCUGGAAGUGAUUGCUUACCUGGUUUGGUGGUGCCUUUAGCGGUGAACAAAGCCAGAGCGAAUACUCCUGGGCCACCGGCUCUAAUUGGUAGUGCUGGGGGUGGAAGGGAUGGGGAGGGGUGUGAUUCCCAUAGGUGGGGGUGGAUUUCUACAAAAGCUAACCUGACAAAGAAAUUGGCUAGCCAAAUGCCAGUCCUCCCCGACCCCCUCCCUACCUUUAUUUCCAAAGGUUAUGCUCAAGCGGGGCCUUAGCAAUAGCUCCAAUUUGUAAUUCUAAUUUCCUUGGAAAUAGGGCUAAAUAGAGCAUUUGUCAUUUCUCUCCAUGUGGAUUACCGGCCGCAGAUGAGGAUUUAUGGCCUGAGCUGCUUCGGCCUCAGGAGCCUGUCUCUGGGGCUGAGAUAGGGUGUCUGAGCACAGAUUCGGGGAGAGGGUGUUGCAUAGGGAGAAGGGGCUGGGUGUUGUCAGUUAAAAAUAUCUCAAACAUUUUUUUCUCUAAAUCUAGAAGAGAGAAAAAACCAUGUAUCCUGUUAAAGCUUCAGGUUGCCUGGUUAUGAAUAAAAUAAGAAGCAGGAAAAUGUUCAAAGGGAAAUGCUUUGAGCACUGUGGGAGUGGUUUUUCUGCCCUGGAUAUUUCUUCUGGGAGAGAGAAUGCCUUGACCUCAUAGGUCAGUUGAAGACCAAGGCCCGGGUAGGAGCUCAUGCGGCUCCCCGGGGUAGCUUGUAUGGGGAACUAGGAGAAAAUCUGGCCCACCUUGUUGGAAGCUAGAGUUUGAGAAGUUUGCCAUUGGCAUUUAGAGUCCAUCUUUGCAGCCGUUGGUGCAUUCUGAAAAUACAUUUUAGCCCUUACUCGUUGCCAGACUCUGUGCUAGGCACCAGGGAAACCAGUGGGGAACCCACACCAAAUGGUUCUGCAGCUCCAUGGAGUUUGUAGCCUGGUGGGGGAGACAGACAUUGAUCAAGGAAUUACAAAAAUAAAUGUCAAAUUACCCCCUUGCUAAGCUCUCCAGAGGAGAGGUGCCUAAUGCAUAAAGGGAUUUAUACUCCUGGGACAGCUCAGAGUGGGCUUCACAGAUGCUGAAACUGAGAUACAUAUGGAGGAAGAAUCCGGUUUACUUUCUUUUUUUAAACUUUCAUUUUAAGUUCAGGGGUACAAGCACAAGUUUGUUACAUAGGUAAACUUGUGUCAUGGGGGUUUGUUGUACAGAUUAUUUCAUCAAGCAGGUAUUAAGCCUAGUACCCAUUAGUUAUUUUUCCUGAUUCUCUCCCUCCUCCCCACCUCCACCCUCUGAAAGACCGCAGUGUAUGCUGUUCGCCUCUGUGUGUCCAUGUAUUCUCAAUCAUUUAGCUCUCACUUAUAAGUGAGAACAUGCAGUAUUUGUUUUUCUGUUCCUGUGUUAGUUUGCUGAGGAUAAUGGCCUCCAGCUCCAUCCAUGUCCCUGAAAAGGACAUGAUCUCAUUUUUUUUAUGGCUCCAUAGUAUUCCGUGGUGUAUAUGUACCACAUUUUCUUUAUUCAGUCUAUCAUUGACGGAUAUUUAGGUUGAUUCCAGAAUGGCUGCUAUUAAAACGUCAAAAAAUGACAUGCUGAUGAGAUUUCAGAGAAAAAGGAAUGCUUAUACACUGCUGGUGUGAGUUUAAGUUAGUUUAGCCAUUGUGGAAGGCAGUAUGGCAAUUCCUCAAAGACCUAAAGACAGAAAGCCAUUCAACCCAGCAAUCCCAUUACUGGGUAUAUACCCAAAGGAAUAUAUAUAUAUAUAUUUGUUUGUUUGUUUGUUUGUUUUGUUUUGUUUUUUGAUUUUUGUUUUUUUGGAGCCAGAGUCUCGCUCUAUCGCCCAGGCUGGAGUGCAGUGGUGCGAUCUCGGCUCACGGCAAGCUCUGCCUUCCGGGUUCACGCCAUUCUCCUGCCUCAGCCUCCCGGGUAGCUGGGACUACAGGUGCCUGCCACCGCGCCUGGCUAAUUUUUUAUUUUUAUUUUUAAUAGAGAUGGGGUUUCACUGUGUUAGCCAGGAUGGUCUUGAUCUCCCGACCUUGUGAUCCACCUGCCUUGGCCUCCCAAAGUGCUGGGAUUACAGGCGUGAGCCACUGCACCUGGCCUACCCAAAGGAAUAUUAAUCAUUCUAUUGUAAAGACACAUGCACACAUAUGUUCAUUGCAACACUAUUCACAGUAGUAAAGACAUGGCAUCAACCUACUUUUGAGGUCUUCAAGUGUUGGGGGUGGGAAAGAGUGUACUGGGCCCCACCAUUGCUGCCAGUCUUGACUGUGGCAUGUGGGGCAGGUAAGUUACUUCUCCUCUUGGAGCCCCAGUUGUCUGGUCUGUAAAAUAGAACUAAUCAAAUCCACUCCACAGUUUCUGUGAUAAGAAUAGAGAGUUAAGUGCAGGUCGGAUAUCUGGCAGGCCCUAAACCUUAACAGGUGAGAAGCAGAGUUCUGAUUUCUUGAUGGCAAUGCCAUACCCCUUUGAGCAGAAGGUCACUCAUGGUCCCUGAUAAAUACAGUGUCACCUUUGAAUAGGACUUGAUAGGGCUGGGCUAUGUAUUUUGCAGGGUUUGGCCCACUUUAACAUUCUGUGAGGGUGGCAGAGUGGCAUCUGUCUGUGUUGCAGGAAGAAGCUGACUUCAAGGGGUUAGUAACCCCCCUCCUGUGUGUGCACAGUUGGUAAGGGGCAGAGGUGGAGUUCGAAUCCAGAUUGAGGCUGUCCAAAGUUAGUGUAUUUUCUCCUCCUGCUUCCUUGUCUUCGUGGCGUGGGGAAAGGGUCACGUAACCCCUCCAAGCCUCAGUUUCCCACGACCGACAUGGAGAACUACGCUGCACAAUGGGGCGGUGACCAACACAUUCAUGUGUUCACUCUUCAGGGCACAUUACACUGUGCGGGGCCAGGCUCUGGGCUUGGACACAGAGGGAAGGAAGGACUCAAGGCCACCCCUCAGGGCUGCGUUCUAGUGUGGGAAGACAAACACAUGCCAGGAAAUGAGGGGACGCCUGAUACUGCAGGACCUGGUCAGCGCCAUGAAGGACAGCAGGGAAAACGGUGGAAAGACUGUGCAAGUGCAGGGCAGCACUUCAUCUGUGCUGCUGGCAGCUUCUCUCUGUUAAGAUGACUUUGAGCAGAGACUGGAAUGAGUAAAGGAGAGAGCCACAGAGAUGACUGUUGGCAUCCAAGAGUUCAAACCAAUGGCAAAUGGAAAACAUUCAGAAAAAUAAAAAUGAACAAUACAGCAAUAAAACAUGACACAAAUUAAAAAGAAACAAUUCAGUAUAAUGACUACUGACAUAGCAUUUGCAUUGUAUCAGGUAUUACAGUAAUCUAGAGAUGAUUUAAAGUAUACGGAAGGAUGUUUGCAGGUUCUAUGCAAAUAGUACACCACUUUGUAUUAAGGAUUGAGCAUCUGGGAUUGUGAUAUCCUCAGGAGGUCCCAGAACCAAUCCUCUAUGGACACUGAAGGAUGACUGUAGUUUCCUACUUCUGUGUAACAAAUUACCACAAAUUUAGCAGCUUAAAGCAGUGUAAAUUUGUUAUUUUACAUGUCUGAAGGUCAGAAGUCCAAAAUAGGUCUCACUGGGGUAAAACAAGGUGUCAGCAGGGCUGUGUCCCUUCUGGACUCUGGAGAGAACCUGUUACCCUGCUUUUUCCAGCUUUUGAGGCUACCUGCAUUCCUCAGCUCAUGGCUCCUUCUACCAUCAUGAAAGCCAGCAGCACAAUCUCUCUCUCACUCUGACUCCUCUCUGCCCCCUCCUCUGCUGGAAAGGAACCUUGUGGCUGUGUUGGGCCCACCUAGGUAAUCUGGAAUCAUCUCUUUAGGGUCAGCUGAUUACCAUACUUUGUUCCUUCAGCAACCUUGACUCCCCUUUGCCAUGUAACCUAGCAUAGCACAGAUUCUGGGGGUUAAAACAUGAAUAUCUUUAAUGGAGGCUUUAAUGGAAGCACCUUCUUUCUCAGUGAGAAGUCCUGCUGGGGAGUCAGGGGGCUUGCCAUGAAGCCGCGGUCCUGCUGCCUAACUGCUGGGAGACUGUGGCUCUUCAUCUCUCUGAGCCUUCCAUCUUUAAAAUGGGCACUGAAACUUAGAUUUAUAAUUGUGCAGUAGACUUCAAAAAGGUUUGCUGGGAUGAAUUGAAUUUCCGGAGUCUGGUUUAUCCUGAUGAGUUUGCCGCUCAGUCCAGAAGUCAUGUUACUCAGCAGGGGUAAAUCUUGACUUUGCCAGAAUGGGUUAGGGAUGUGGGAAAUCUAAACCCAGAUGAAAAAAUUGGUUCGGCAUAAAGCUUGGUAGGAAGUAUGGGGGUAUUGGGAGCUGGCGUAAGUGGGAUGGGUAUUUGGGUCAUCCAGGGUUAUAGGAUUUCUUCAGAAAAUAAGGUACAAAGAGAAACUGCUUUUGGCCUCCGUCACACUGCGGCUGAAGACUGCCACUAGAUAGCAGAAUGUUCAGCCAGGCUGGAAAUGGUUAAACAAAAUGUUACAUCUGGCUGGAAUGGACCUUAAGGUCACUUCAUAGAAGUCCACAUGCAAUGCUUGAAUCUCUUCUUCAAGAGCCCUGAGAGUUGUAGCCUAGACUGUUCAUGAACCUUCUUAGUGAUAGGGAACAACACACGGCAGCUAUCCUUAGAGAGUCUUACGCUGACCACAUUUCCUUUCAUUGACCUGAGCUCAGUCUCGCUGUCUCUUUCCACAGUAUUAGUUUUUCUCCAUGAGCGCCACAGAGAAUGACCAGACCACCCAAGCCAGGGCUCUCCUAGCAGCUGACCACCAUCCAUCAUCACUCUCAGAGAUGUUACUGGUCCAUCACCAAGCAGCCGCACCCACACGUUGCAGGGGUUCCCUUGGGUAAGGAGCCUGGCCAGGGCCUCUGGGUUCUGAGCACAUCUCCUGUUGGUCAUCACAGACCACAGAGAAAUCAGGCAGAACUCUUCCUCAGGAAAAUAAUAGAGGGCCCAGUGGAGUCCCUAAGUUCCUCAGAUAGAAGGAGGAAUGGGCAGGGUGGGAUCGGGGCAGAGACCUUAAAUCCUGCCACUGUUUUCUACUGCAUUUGGAAGCAGCCCAGGAGCUCCAAGGAUUGAGACAGCUUGGUCCAAAUGUCAGAAGGAGACUUCAGUGUAUCUGAGGACCUGAAAGAGGCAGGAAUUCUAGUCUUAUAUAAUACAGACUUGAAUAGAAAGCAAAUUUUCCUGAAUGUAUUUCUCAUAAGAAGAAUCACCUUAUAAUAGAAAGCAGUUUUUCCUAAAUGUAUUUCUCAUAAGAAGAAUCACCUAAUAAUUGAGUCCUUACAAAAUUUUUAUUAUGUGGCACCAUCUCAGUUGUUUUAUUUUGUGACAACAGGUUACAACAGGUUCUUUGAGGAAGGGGCACAUUUGCCUGUGAUAUAAACAUAGUAGUGCUAGUUUUAGACACUUGUAGCAGUCACUCAAUGGAAUUGGCUUCAUGCACACACACAAAGCUGCUUAAUGGAUUAAAUCAUUUUUCCUGGGGCAAUGUUCUUACAAAUGCAAGUUAAACUGCUGUGAACAAUUAUUUUAAAGAUCUAUGAAAGAAAAACCUCAGUAGAGUUAGUGGUUAUAGUGUAAGGAUCCUCAAAGAUGGAUGGGUAUUUGGGGCCUGGGACAGAGUUUUCAGUGACAGCAUCACGGAUGGCUUCAAAAGAUGUAUCUCUCCCAAGCAACCUAGAUGUAUGAAAAUACGGUGCAUGAGAAUACAGGAUGCUCUGGAAAACUGAGUUGAGGAAUUAGAGUGUAUAGAGGCAUCAGAAACAGUGAUAUCAAAGAAUAAAUGGUUUCACCAAACGAGUAUGGCAAAUUAGAAAUAUUUCUAAAUGAACACAUAUGCAGAGUAUUAAAUUUCUAUGUGUAAACUAAAUUAAUACAUUAAAUGUUAGAAAUAGACACUUAGCUUUUCAAAGAACAGGCACAUUCAGUAUUCCAUGUUCACCUGCAAGGGAGGCAGGAGAGGAACCACUGUCCCCAUCUCAUAUUUUUGGAAACUGAGGCACAGAGACCAGCCAUGAGUGGAUGCCAGAACUAAAACCUUAGGCCUGUCCCCUACACCACCCCACUCUUUUUUUUUAUUUUUUUUAUUUUUUAUUUUUAUUUUUUUUUUGAGACGGAGUCUCGCUGUCGCCCAGGCUGGAGUGCAGUGGCGCAAUCUCGGCUCACUGCAGGCUCCGCCCCCUGGGGUUCACGCCAUUCUCCUGCCUCAGCCUCCCGAGUAGCUGGGACUACAGGUGCCCGCCACCUCGCCCGGCUAAUUUUUUGUAUUUUUAGUAGAGACGGGGUUUCACCGUGUUAGCCAGGAUGGUCUCGAUCUCCUGACCUCGUGAUCCGCCCGCCUCGGCCUCCCAAAGUGCUGGGAUUACAGGCGUGAGCCACCGCGCCCGGCCCACCACCCCACUCUUAAGAGAAGCAAACUGGCACAAAAGAUUAGUCCAACUCCUGAAAAGCCUGUCCUGAAAAUGACAGCAGGCCAAAGACAAGAGACACCUGGGCUGCCUGGAGUAAGUGGGUGGAAAUCUGCGACCCCCAAAAGGUCCCUUCCAGCCCUACCUUCUGAGGACUGAGCCCAGGGAGAACUAACCACUACCAAGGGUUUUCUCUGUGGCUUCCUGAUCCUCCUGGCACAAUUUAAAAAAUUAUUUCAGUUUGGCUAUUUUACUUCUUAAGGAUUAAAAAUGAGUCUUUAAAAGUGUGGAGAAACAAACUCAAAACCUCACGUGAAAUACAUAGCAAAAAUGAAAUUCCAGUAAAAUAUAAGGACAUUGAAACAAAGAAACAAAAAUAUUUGCCUGGCCUGAAGAAGAUUCCUGUACAAAUAAUCCCCAAACUAGUUAGUGUCUACAGAAGCUGUUUUUUCAUUCAUUGUAAGGUAAGGUAUGGUAUCAUUUGAAGAGAGAUUUAAACAAAGUCGAACAACAUACUGCUGUUUUCAGUUUUUCUCAUAAUGUACAAGCAUUAAAAUUCAAAAGAACUUGAGGUAUUCCGCAUGGAUCUAGAUACUGCUUAAGAAAUAUUGAAAAUGUUUAUUAGUGAUGGUGAUUUAUAUGAUCAAGUUAAAAAAUUUUAUAGCAUCUUCUGUGAUAUAACAGGUUAUAUAUGUAACUCUCUUAUAGUGUUUCAAUGUGGUAAUGUGAAAAUUAAGGUUCAUUUCCAAACCUAAGUAUUUACAAUUUUAUUGAUAAUUCCCUUCUCCACAUUAAAGUUAAUUAAAAACUAAGAAACUACAUUAAUUCAAAAAAGGUUGUUUUAUCUGGCAUUAUGUCAACAGAGUGCAUAUUACAUGAAAAUCUUGAUUAUAGACCAUAAUUAAUGCUUUUCCUGGAAUGAAGGCAAGGAAAUUUCAUGGAAAAAUAUGUAAUCAUUAUGAGAUGUUUUAAAAAAGCCAUUUAAUAAAUUUGGACACUGCCUCUCUUUCAGGGGCCAACCCUGGCAGAGCUGGGGCAGGACCGUGGAAGCUGGCGGGGCAAUACAAACUUGGCUGCAAUGCCAAAUGAUGAGGACAAGACUAGGGGGUGAAUAAAGGCUGAGAGCCUUCCGCCCUGAGGUUCUUGAAAAAAUGGUGGCCCACACCUGUAAUCCCAGCACUUUGGGAGGAUUGUUUGAGAUCAGGAGUUUGAGACCAGCCAGGGCAACAUAGUGAGACCUCAUCUUAAUAAAAUAAAAUAAUUAAAUAAAUAUAAAUAUAAAUUUUAAUUUGGAAAAGAAGAAAAAAAUGGUCUAUGCUUGCUCUCUCGCUACUUCCUUGAGCUCCUGUUCACUACUCGGUCUAGGUUUGAACGCAGUUUGAUUUUGGGCUAAUUACUCUCAGCUCCUUUAUCAAUAAAGCAGAGAUAACAAACAUAUCCCCCAAAGGUGCUUUGAAAAUUGAAUGCACCAAAGGCAGUCUACAGAGGUUAAGGUCGCACAGAUGGAGGUUAAUAUCCUGAUUCCCAUGCUUGCUGAGUGAUUCCUUAAGCUCUCUGAGCUUUAGUUCCUUAGCUGUAAGGAGAUCCCUCCCCGCCUCUGGCUGAACUGGUCGGCUGGCACGGUGGCUCUGAGCUUCAGUUGCUGGAACGACCCCAGACCUGUUCUUGUACCAUUCCUUUACUCACUGUUACAUUCCACAGAAUAUUUGAGCAUCUAUUGUGUCUGUAAAUGUGAAUACACUGAUAAAUAAUCAAAUAAAAUAAAACAAAGAGAAUAAUGAUCAGUGGGAGCAUUGGGUCCAGGAGGUCCUGGGCAUGCUCCUUGAACUUCUCACAUCCUUUCUUAACUGUCAGUGUAGGGGCUGCUGUCCCCCACCCAGGCCUGUGCUGGUUCAUCCUUGCAUGCUCAGCACUGAGGCAGCACCCCUGACCUAGGUGGCUGCUCAGUAAAUGUGUAUAGAAUGAAUGAAUCCUUUCUAUGGUAGGCUAUAGGUUUAAGAGAGCUGAACUUUGGGGCCAGAAACUGUUCAGACUCAGAAAAAUUUACAGAGGUUCAAAUUGGUUUCAAGUAAUAAUGACCCCUACCUAGCCUUUAAGAGGCAGCCUCUUCCGGGGUCACCUCCUUUCUGAGGCCUUCUGUUGUUUCCAUGGCUCACAAAUCCAUUUUUCUCUUACCUCUUUCAGCAUUUGCCAUCCAUAGUGGACAACAUUUGAUACUGACUACAUGAUUCUUCCUUGCCCAUGUCUAACUAUUGCUCUCUAGCGUCCUAUAAGCUCCUGGUCUUAUCUGAGAUGGCUCUGAAGUUUCCUGCAUUCACAUCAUUUUGAUUUUGCUUAAAACUUUUGAGUUUGGGGCAUCAUCUCCAAAAAUAGUUUAACUUCUCUAAGCCUCCAUUUUCUCUUUUAUCUAAUGGAGAUAAAAAUACCUACCUGAGAAGGUUGACCACAUGAACUGACUCAUUCAUUCAGAAAGUAUUUUUCCAGCAUCUACUAUGUGCCAGCCACUGUUCUAGGUGCUUGGAAUAGAUCUGUGAGCAAAAGAGAAAAAAUAACCUCUUCAUUCAUAGAUUGUACAUUCUAGUUAGGAGUGGCAGGCAGGUGAUAGAUAUAAAAUGUAAGACAAUGUUAAUAGUAUGUUAAGCAGUGAUAAAACCUACAAAGAAAAACAGAGGAGGAGAUGGAUGAUGGAAAGACUGACCACAAAUUAGCAACUUAAAAAUAUCAUGGAAAUAUUUGUUUAUUAUUAUUAUUAUUUUUUUUUUUUUUUUUUUUGAGACGGAGUCUCGCUCUGUCACCCAGGCUGGAGUGCAGUGGCGGGAUCUCGGCUCACUGCAAGCUCCGCCUCCCGGGUUCACGCCAUUCUCCUGCCUCAGCCUCCCAAGUAGCUGGGAAUACAGGCGCCCGCCACUACGCCCGGCUAAUUUUUUAUAUUUUUAGUAGAGACGGGGUUUCACCGUUUUAGCCGGGAUGGUCUCGAUCUCCUGACCUCGUGAUCCGCCCGCCUCGGCCUCCCAAAGUGCUGGGAUUACAGGCAUGAGCCACCGUGCCCGGCCUAUUAUUAUUUUUUAUUUUAUUUAUUUACUUAGUUUUGAGAUGGAGUCUUGCUCUGUCACUCAGGCUGGAGUGCCGUGGCACGACCUUGGCUCACUGCAACCUCCGCCUCCUGGGUUCAAGUGAUUCUCCUGUCUCAGUCUCCUGAGUAGCUGGAAUUACAGGUGUGCACCACCACAUCCAGCUAAUUUUGGUACUUUUAGUAGAGAUGGGUUUUUGCCAUGUUGGCCAGGCUGGUCUCGAACUCCUGAUCUCAGGUGAUCCGCCUGCCUUGGCCUCCCAAAAUGCUGGGAUUACAGGUGUGAGCCACCGUGCCCAGCCUAUUAGUUUAUUUUUAAAAUCUAUACUAACAAAAAUAAAGCAAUCAUCAAUUCAGUACACUCUCAUAAGCUGCCCUAAACUUCCACAAAGGCAGCAUCCAGCACUCCCACAUGUGUUGGCCUUGGCGUUGAUUUCUCCAUGGCGAUUUUCAGAAAUGAGAAUGCUGUGUCUGCGGUCAGAGAUGAACACAUUCUUGUUGGAUUGAAAAGAAAGCAGAUACAAAAGGAAAUGGAGAAACAUCUGGCUGUUCCCAGUCCUUCUCUGCUGGGUCAGAACAAACUCACACAUCAGUCAGGGGUUGUUUUUCAUGAACAGAAUGGCUAGUGGUGGCUUUUCAUUGAAUUAGGAACUGGGAGGGGCUAAUGAUCCAGAUGAGUGGGGUUGAACUGGGAGGGGCUAAUGAUCCAGAUGAGUGGGGUUGACUUCUAGGACAUUUCCAAUCCAGACACUCACAAUAAAGUAUGAGGUAACCUCCUGGAGAAUUCAGGAGGCCUCCUCCAAUUCUCCUCCAAUAUGGUAAGAUUCUUUGACCCCAAUUUCUUUGGGCAUUGAACAGGUCAAUAAUUAUGAUAACUCAGAAUGGGGAUUCUUCAUCUACCAUGUAGGAAAGACCAUUUGUGAUUUUAUCUAACCCAGAAUUUGGCGUUAUGUAGUUGCCGUGUCUGUUUGUGUGUUCUCUUCAAGUGGUGGCAAAUUAUUCUUAGCAUGAACUGGGGCAUUUGUUCACCAAAUUCUCCUUCAGCUCUUGACCUGUGCCUGGCACAAGAAAGACAUCCUACUAAUUCUUGCCCUCGUGAAGCUUUUAUUCUGGUGAAGAAGACAGGCAUUUUUAAGUGAAGGAUUGCAAUAUUGCUUGGUAAGUGCAGUGUGUCCAGAGUGGAUGACAGAGAUAGGAUGUGAGGGGGAAGAAGUAGGCAGGACCUAGAUGAUGAAUGGAGUCCUAAGUCCUGUUAACAGAGUAGGGAAUGUUUCAGCAGUGGAGUGAGAGAACUGGCUUUGCACUGGAAGGGUCACUCUGCCUGUGGAGUCGAGUUUGGAAUGGAAAGGCAAGCCUCUUAAGGAAGGAGAUGAGUUAGGAGGCUAGUGAAGCUAUUAUACUGGAAUACAGAAAAUUGUGCAUGUCCUUCAACCCAGAGUGUUCAACUUUAAUGUAUUUAAUACAUUUUUGAUUGUUUUAACCUCUGGACUUGAAAACAUUGUCCAAUAUUUUGACAGAUCAUAGUUUUGUUAUGUUCCAGGUUUUUUUUUUUUUGCCGUAUUCAUUUUCUGCCUUAGGCCCUAGAUGUCUUAGCUGGUCAUAUCUCUACCACUGGAGAGUUGAGUUGCCAUGGAUUAUUUCCCUGAUCCUGAUUAAUUCGAUUCCAAUUCACUCUGCAAACGUGCACUGAGGGCCUGCCAAGUGCCCCAUCCCAUCCCAGGUGCUGCUGAUAUGAUGACAAGUAUGAAGUGGUCCCCUGGGGAUGUGAAUUUCUGUUUUGAGUCAAUGGAGAAUUAAUAGGAAAACUUUGGACAAGCAUCAAAUUCAGUUAAAUGAAAUCAGAAAGUGUUGUACCUGUGGUUCUCAAUGAUCCCUCAUAACAACCCUCUGAGGGAGAUGUGCUUUAAAUUGCUUUGGAGAAGCCAAUAUUGAUGCCUAGAGCUGUGAGGACACUUGCACAAGGCUGCAGUUAGGUUUUAUCAAUGAGGUGUGAAUCCAGGCCCCCGGACCCAGUCAAAGAUCAUGGAUGGAAAGAGUUCAGCAGGUGCCUGGGUGGGGAGCACAGGGCUGGCCUAAGUGUGCUUCUGUCUGGGAUCUCCAUGUAAGUUGGGAUACUACCCAGGGAGUUGCUUGUCUAGGUCCCAGCGGGAACGAUGAAAACAAUUUCAAUAAGGCCAUGACAGUGAAGAAUCCCCAGAUGUUUCACCCUGAAAGCACUGUUUAUUUCUGUCUUCUCCCAGUCUGGGGGCCCUGGAGCCACCUGGUAAGGACCACACCAACCACAGUUCAACCCAUACAUAUGUUUACAUGGGGUCCUCUCUCAGGUGAGCCAGGCUCCAUGGGUCAGUGAGACAGAAGAGGCUGGCCCUGCCUUUCUGGAUAGACUCCCGCUGAGCUCUGAGCUCUGAGAUGAGCUGGCCCAGGAGAUUCAGGGACAUCACCGACCUCCCUAGAGACCAGAGCUGGCCAGGGAUGCCUGUGUGUCCCCCGACUCUGAGGAGGUGGAAUCUGGAUGGGCGUUUUACUGGAACGUUGCAGCAAGAAUCAAGCCUGGAACUGAAAGACUCACUCUUACCAUCCCCAGUGCCUCCAGAUCCUGUGGGACAAUGUGAUUCUGAUGUGAGUAGCAGCAGGAGGGAAGGGAGAUCCUCUCCCCGGCUAGUGACACAUGGGAAUGGUCCACAUCAGUGACAAGGACAAACUCUCCUAGGGAGAGUAGGGAACAUGGGUCCUGAUGCGUGGUGUUUGGGGUUUCAAGGGAUGCAAGAGGCCUCCAGGAGGCUGGGAUGAGCUGGGCUUGGCACUGCUUGGAGAAGGUUCUGGAGCCUAGUGCAAUCAAAGAUGGAAGAUGAGGAGCUGCUCUUAGACACAAAGCCAGGGGAUUACCAGGAGAUUGCCAUUGUCCAGCGUAUUCUUGGGAGAAGGGAAAAUUGGAAGGAGUGAGUGAACCCCCAGGUUGGCAGCCAGAGAAGGAUAUGGACGCUUGAGGAACAGCAAUGCUGAGCGACUCUAUUGAGCCCCCUUUUACUGACGUCCCAAGGAGACAUCAGGGACAAACAUGUUGGAAGGUGUUGAGGAAGGACAAACGGAACCACCACUGAGAUGUGUUCAUUUAUUAGCUUUUGAGAGUUUAAAUGGAAAUAUCUUCCCGUUUCUGUCCUGUAGGGAGAGGUACACUGCGCUGAGCAAACACUUUCUGUUUCCGAAAUAGACUCAUUGUCUGUCUGCAUGGGGAGGAACUCCUGGUGAUGACCGGUUUCCUCACUGCUGCAGAAGUUCAUCUUCAGGAAAGGAGUGGUUUAAAAAUGGAUCAGAACUUGCACAGACUCAUGGUCUAGGACAGUCGGGAAGGCCCCGCUGAUGGAUCCAUUAGCUCAACACUUGAUUUCACACAGGAGAAAAUGGAGCCCAGUGGAAGGAAAUGACCUGCUCAACAUCAUGUAGCAGGUUCCUGAUUGUCCUGGGGUGCUUGAUUCUGGCUGUCCUGACCACAUUCAAGGAGUAUGAGACUGUCUCGGGAGACUGGCUUCUGUUACUGGAGACAUUUGCUAUUUUCAUCUUUGGAGCCGAGUUUGCUUUGAGGAUCUGGGCUGCUGGAUGUUGCUGCCGAUACAAAGGCUGGCGGGGCCGACUGAAGUUUGCCAGGAAGCCCCUGUGCAUGUUGGACAUCUUUGUGCUGAUUGCCUCUGUGCCAGUGGUUGCUGUGGGAAACCAAGGCAAUGUUCUGGCCACCUCCCUGCGAAGCCUGCGCUUCCUGCAGAUCCUGCGCAUGCUGCGGAUGGACCGGAGAGGUGGCACCUGGAAGCUUCUGGGCUCAGCCAUCUGUGCCCACAGCAAAGAACUCAUCACGGCCUGGUACAUCGGUUUCCUGACACUCAUCCUUUCUUCAUUUCUUGUCUACCUGGUUGAGAAAGACGUCCCAGAGGUGGAUGCACAAGGAGAGGAGAUGAAAGAGGAGUUUGAGACCUAUGCAGAUGCCCUGUGGUGGGGCCUGAUCACACUGGCCACCAUUGGCUAUGGAGACAAGACACCCAAAACGUGGGAAGGCCGUCUGAUUGCCGCCACCUUUUCCUUAAUUGGCGUCUCCUUUUUUGCCCUUCCAGCGGGCAUCCUGGGGUCCGGGCUGGCCCUCAAGGUGCAGGAGCAACACCGUCAGAAGCACUUUGAGAAAAGGAGGAAGCCAGCUGCUGAGCUCAUUCAGGCUGCCUGGAGGUAUUAUGCUACCAACCCCAACAGGAUUGACCUGGUGGCGACAUGGAGAUUUUAUGAAUCAGUCGUCUCUUUUCCUUUCUUCAGGAAAGAACAGCUGGAGGCAGCAUCCAGCCAAAAGCUGGGUCUCUUGGAUCGGGUUCGCCUUUCUAAUCCUCGUGGUAGCAAUACUAAAGGAAAGCUAUUUACCCCUCUGAAUGUAGAUGCCAUAGAAGAAAGUCCUUCUAAAGAACCAAAGCCUGUUGGCUUAAACAAUAAAGAGCGUUUCCGCACGGCCUUCCGCAUGAAAGCCUACGCUUUCUGGCAGAGUUCUGAAGAUGCCGGGACAGGUGACCCCAUGGCGGAAGACAGGGGCUAUGGGAAUGACUUCCCCAUCGAAGACAUGAUCCCCACCCUGAAGGCCGCCAUCCGAGCCGUCAGAAUUCUACAAUUCCGUCUCUAUAAAAAAAAAUUCAAGGAGACUUUGAGGCCUUACGAUGUGAAGGAUGUGAUUGAGCAGUAUUCUGCCGGGCAUCUCGACAUGCUUUCCAGGAUAAAGUACCUUCAGACGAGAAUAGAUAUGAUUUUCACCCCUGGACCUCCCUCCACGCCAAAACACAAGAAGUCUCAGAAAGGGUCAGCAUUCACCUUCCCAUCCCAGCAAUCUCCCAGGAAUGAACCAUAUGUAGCCAGACCAUCCACAUCAGAAAUCGAAGACCAAAGCAUGAUGGGGAAGUUUGUAAAAGUUGAAAGACAGGUUCAGGACAUGGGGAAGAAGCUGGACUUCCUCGUGGAUAUGCACAUGCAACACAUGGAACGGUUGCAGGUGCAGGUCACGGAGUAUUACCCAACCAAGGGCACCUCCUCGCCAGCUGAAGCAGAGAAGAAGGAGGACAACAGGUAUUCCGAUUUGAAAACCAUCAUCUGCAACUAUUCUGAGACAGGCCCCCCGGAACCACCCUACAGCUUCCACCAGGUGACCAUUGACAAAGUCAGCCCCUAUGGGUUUUUUGCACAUGACCCUGUGAACCUGCCCCGAGGGGGACCCAGUUCUGGAAAGGUUCAGGCAACUCCUCCUUCCUCAGCAACAACGUAUGUGGAGAGGCCCACGGUCCUGCCUAUCUUGACUCUUCUCGACUCCCGAGUGAGCUGCCACUCCCAGGCUGACCUGCAGGGCCCCUACUCGGACCGAAUCUCCCCCCGGCAGAGACGUAGCAUCACGCGAGACAGUGACACACCUCUGUCCCUGAUGUCGGUCAACCACGAGGAGCUGGAGAGGUCUCCAAGUGGCUUCAGCAUCUCCCAGGACAGAGAUGAUUAUGUGUUCGGCCCCAAUGGGGGGUCGAGCUGGAUGAGGGAGAAGCGGUACCUCGCCGAGGGUGAGACGGACACAGACACGGACCCCUUCACGCCCAGCGGCUCCAUGCCUCUGUCGUCCACAGGGGAUGGGAUUUCUGAUUCAGUAUGGACCCCUUCCAAUAAGCCCAUUUAAAAGAGGUCACUGGCUGACCCCUCCUUGUAAUGUAGACAGACUUUGUAUAGUUCACUUACUCUUACACCCGACGCUUACCAGCGGGGACACCAAUGGCUGCAUCAAAUGCAUGCGUGUGCGUGGUGGCCCCACCCAGGCAGGGGCUUCCCACAGCCUCUUCCUCCCCAUGUCACCACAACAAAGUGCUUCCUUUUCAGCAUGGUUUGCAUGACUUUACACUAUAUAAAUGGUUCCGCUAAUCUCUUCUAGGAUACACAUUUAUCUGCUGUUCUUACUUUUAAUCACGAUUGGACCAGUACAGGGAGAAAUUACUGAUGAGCCAUGCUAUUUGUCUGUUUGGUUGGCUGGUUUGGGUUUUGGUUUGGUAAGCAGAGAAAGUAGUUUAAGUUAUUUCUAGGAUCACUGCCCUCUUGUGUAAAACGCUCCAGCAAUUAACUGUUUUUGAAAGCAAGGAAAUAAUUUUCUCAACAAAACCACAUUGUGUAUCAGUGGGGCUGCCUACUGAGCUAACAUUAGGAAAGGAAUGAGAUAGUCAUUGUGUCUCUAAAACAAAGAAUUUAAACAAAUAUUUAAGGCAAAACCUUUUAAAAGCUCUCCAAAAGACCUCACUUGGCCUGAUGUUACUUAGUAUCAUGCCUCAGUUUCCUUAUCUGUAAAAAGUGGUGGUAAUCCCAAGUGUAGCAUUUCUGAUGAGUUAUGAAUUGGCAGGGAGAAAACACACACACACACACACACACACACACACACACACACAUACACAAAGUUAAAAUAGUUUCCAAUUUAUGUAGCCAAGGACAAUGGAAUUUAUCAGAAGUGAAGUGCCCCUCUGGGCAGGAGCUGAGUUCAGUGCCUUUAAAAUGAAUUUCCAACUCUCAUUUCUUCCCAUGAUACUGAAGUACAAAAUAUCCAUCUAAAAUAGAAAUUAAAGUCAAGAAGGCACACAGAAAUUUUCUAGUCCAAGGACUUCCUUUUAUAAAUGAAGAAUCUUAGGCUCAGGUAAAGUGACAUACCCAGAGUCACUCAGUUGUCCCAUAGAGAACCAGGACUCAAAAGUCAGGUCUGCCCACUCUCCCUGACCUUGUUUCCCCUCACCACACCAUUCUUCCAUUUAUAUAAUGCAUCCUAGAGAUUGUGUCAAGAUAUAUGACUUUGUGUCGCGUGGAAAGCACCCAGUUUAUCCAGCAGGAGGGGGAUUUCCACUUUUAUUGCAAAACAUGCUUGCUUGAUGCAAUGCAUUUCAGAUCUAGAAAAAAAUAAUGCAAGCAAGCUACAUUUACAGAUGUGUAAACAGGCAAAAUUUCCAGAACCGUCCAAUUUUACUUUUCCAAAUUUAUGGAACCAACCCAGAUUUUUUAAAUGAAAAUACUAAAACCAUAUGUAACCGUAAGACAAGCUAAAAUGUAAGCAGACAGCCUGGGAAGCACUGCCCUACUGUACAGGUGUGAUAUUAAGCACAAGCCAUCCUCUGGCCUCUUAUGAGAUGUUGUUAUUCUCUGAAAAACUUUGAUGGAAAAGGUUUCUGUUAGGCUUAGACUGAAUUAGCUAAAUGACCAUGCCACAGUAUUAUUGUAUCACUCUUCUCACACACCUAGGCACUGGUUGUGGAUAGUUGCCAUGGUGACAAUCAAGAUAAUCCAGAUGACCUAAACAAAUGUCUGUAUGCAGCUGACACUGCUAUUCUCCCUCACAGUCUUGUCAAGAGCCACAGUAGCUAUGGCAGACAUUUGGUUGAUGGUUUCAUCAUUUCCUAAUACGAGAGUCUGGCACUAUGUUGGAGAGAGGAAUCACUUCCUCAGAGAUAGGUUCCUUUCAACUCACAUGUCAACAGUUACUGUACAAAAAGCUCAGAAUACAGUAAUGAUUAGAGCUUGACCCCUGACUUUAGGAACUUAGAACCAAAGCCCAAAGUCCCAGGCCAAGGGCAGACAUUGUGAGCAGCAGAAGGGUGUUUUUUAUGGAGAGCCCCAUAAAUGGAUGGGUGUAGACCUUGAAGUCUGAGAUGGGAAAUAUACCAGAAUGCUCAAUGCAUCAGACAUGAAGCCCCACGGGCUUCCAUUUGACAUGCUGGCAAUCUGAAGGACAAAGGGCAUGGGUUAUUUGGGCCUUUUCCCCACUCCUUCAAUAUGGCUGAAAGUGCCAGUGGGGAUUACAACCUAAGAAACCCUAUGCCCCUUCCUGAGGGCUUGAUUAUUGAAUCCUGAUCUUCCUGGAAUCUUUCACUUGAGAUGAUCACCUGCCUAACAUCCAACAUGUUACUAUGCUCUUCUUUAUGUACAUGAGUUACUGGAAACCAACAAUAAAGGAGAGUGAGUCAUACUCUCCACAUAUGCGCCAAUUAAUUUUUUAACUUACUUAUUAGUAUUCUUGAAGAACUUACUAUCUUAAGUAUUUUACCAAUAGAUGAUGCAUUUUCCAGCAACUCAAUGGAGUUCUACCUUAAAGUAUUUACCAUUGAUCCAAAAUUGGAGGAACUACCUUAGAUUCUUUUAAUAACCUAGAAAGGAUUGGAGCUUGUAUUAUUUCCUAAACCAUAGGCAGGCAGUCUAGCUUCCCUGCUGGAUCAUAAGACCAGGACAGCAGAGAUUGGGUUUGUAUUGAUCAGUAGUAGGGAAGUAUUGAUUGUCUAACAUCUAGUAAGUUGUCUUUAUCAGUAUAGACAUAGACAAAAUACAUGUUUUAUGAAUGAAUAAAUAAUAAGAACCUUAAGAGCUGUUUUUUUCCCAUUUAAGAAAACAAAAAGGAAAAGAGAAAAAUGAUCUUCUGGAAUAACUCUGCUUUGAUAUUCUCCUUUUGUUCCCCAAAAAAUAUAUUCCAGAAAGGCAAACCAAACCUGCUCAAGUUGCCUAUGCACAGACAAUCUCAACAAUAUGGCUCACAGUGAGCAAGCAGAAAUUCAGGGUCUGGAAUUGAAUGUGAGUUAUGGGAAGAAACAGUGUGUGCUUUCACAAAGAUCCUUUUGUCAGACAAGGGAACAGCAUGAUAAUCCAAUGGAACUGGUUAACAUGACCCAAGAUGACAUGACCACAGAUAUACUAGUCGUUCUGAAACUUGCCCAAGAAAUUGCAAUCGUUUCAGCAGAACUCCAUGAAAUAUUGACAAAUUAAUUCCAUCAUCAAACUAGGAGUGAUAUUAUCAGGUAAAACUAUGAUCUCAUGUAUGUAUUUGGUCUUUCUGGGUCACAAUGUGACAUGAAAAAUUUUAAAGGUCAUAUUUUAGCAAGAUCAAAAUGAAUUAGAUAAAUCAACUUCACAAAUGUUAAGCGAAACAUGAUCCUAUUGAGCUGAGAAAGAAGUACUUGAGAUCGUUUGAGUUUUGACUAUCAAAUGUCAGCACAAAAGCAAAUAUCAAAAGCUUAAGAAAAAAAUUAUUUCAGGAAAAGAAAAACACAUCAAAUUGAGAAAGUGUUGUUGAAUAACUUUGUUUUUAGAACUGGAAAUUUAGGCUUAUUAGACAUGACAUUGAUAUUACAAAGCCCUAGUUUUCAUGAAAACAUAACUAGAUAACCCCAAGGUGUAUAGGUUAAAAUGAACUAAUUAAUCAACAAUUAUGCAUCCUGUGUCUAUUUUGUGCAAGGUACUUCCUAGACACUGUAGUUUGAAAGAAUAAUUUCCUGUAGAAAAACCUAAUCUAAUAGGACCUACUCAUAAUUUGGCAAAAUCAUCCUCAUAAUUCCAUGCUACUGAAAUGGGGGUGUAAUAAAGAAAAAAUCAUUUGUUUAUUCAUUUAACAGGGUUUAUUAAGCACCAAUAUAUGCCCAGAACUUUGCAGUGCACUGGAAGUUCAGAGAUAAGAAAACCACAGUUUCUGCCAUCAAAAUGCUAGGAAUCUAGAGGUCUCAAACAUCAGAGGUCCCUUCAAACUAUGUCUACCAGGAAAAUAAAAUACCUGAUUUCAUCCCUGCAAACAACUCUAUACAGACAGAAAUGCUUCCUAGCUUGGAAACUAUAGAAAAUUGAACAUGAAAAUGAGAGCAAAGGUUCUACAUCAAAAUGGCAAUGAUCCAAUCAGCCCAGUCAAGGCUGAGUGGGUUGAAUGGGGACUUCGAGUUUGGAUUCAAUGCUUUGAACUUCAUAGCUCCAGAGAAGCUGUGCAAAAAGGGGGGAUUCUAGGGAAUCUGAGGAAGAUUGUUGGAGAAACCAGCUUUCUUCUUGUCUCCUAAUCCCUGCUAAGAUUGAUACCAGUCAAGGAGCUGAGUUACUUUCAUUUCAUUAUGUUGACCAAGAGAAGCUUAUGAUACAGACUAUGACACAGCACCUAUUUCAAGAGAAAGAUGUUACUCUACUUAUGGGAACCUGCAGAUCAAAUUCUCCUGGGGCAAGAGAAGAAAUUUGUUCAGCAGCCUAAGAAGUCAACUGUACUUUGGACAGUGCUGCCAAACACACCCCAGGAUUCUCCCACCCCUGUGCUUUCCCAGAAGAUGCCACAUAGCUGGUAUUUGGUUUUCAUGAAUAACCAAAGAUUCUUCUUUGCUUCCUGAACCCCAGGCAUCCUUAGGAAUUUGCUUCAUGUCCUCACUUGUCCUUGAAGGCUUGUUUUUCAGGAUGAACUUUUAAAGUCUAAGUUGUUUAUAUUCAAAUCAACCCAAUGCUAUUGUUGCUGAUAUUAAACCAUUCCAAACUGAGCCAACUGGCCCCUAAACAAGCCAGCAGGCAGCCCCUCACUAAUGCCCAGUUUAGAACAUGUUAGGACCAGGCUAUCUGCAUAGCUUUAGUGGUUUUAGAAGCCAGUAAUGGCAGUGUAAAAGAGGAAUCAUACAGAGAUGACCUGGAAGAAAAUUUGAGUUUCAGCACAUUCAAAAGCAUUUGACUCUUCUGCCGUGUUUUGAUUUUCAAGUGAGACAAUCAAUGUACACACAAAGCCUCUAGUACAAUGACUGAUGCAUACUAGGGACUGUUAUUUAUGUUAUUUUUUUACAGUAUGCAUGGACUUCAUUGUCUCAGUCUUUGGUGUUACUUAUAAACUCUAAAUUUACACCAAAAAAAUUUUUUUUCAGAAAAAGAAUCGUGGAGAAACAAUCCUAAUUAUUAAAUCAAAUGCUUUCACAAUUGCUUUUUAAAUAAGUACAUCUCUGCAAAUAAAAAUGCUUGCUCUUGUCUACCACAAUAAAGAACAGAAGGAAUCUUGGAAUGAAGAGAGGCAGGAAUGUUGGAUCUCAGUGGCUGAGUUGUGGCAAUUCCAUUGGACAUAUAGUACCAGAUGUUGCACCAUCUGGAUGAUGUGUAGGAGAUAAAGCCAAAUUGCAAAAAUAAAAGACUCAUGAUUUCCCAAGGAAAGUCAACUGUGCAUGGUGGCUAUCAGACAACACCCUAGCAAUGAAUGGGGGAACUUGCAGAAGAAAGAGUUAAUGCUUGCUUAAACCUUCCCUGGGGAGAUUUGUUCCCAGGCUUUCACGGCUUUAACCUCAGCAACCCUGUAAGAAAAUUGUGAUUCAUAUUUUGAUUUGUUAUCAUAGAUGCAAAGAGACAUAAUUUCAUGGAUUCUAAGAUACACAGAGCAAGAAGAGAUUUUGAUCACCCAGAACAACCACCUGUCUUUUUAGAUCAAGAAGCAGAAGCUCAGAGCAAAGAACAUCACACCACGUCCCUCAGUGAUUGAAGCAGUGAUUGAGUCACAGAAUAAAUCUGGAACUCAGGUCUUCUGAUCUUUGCUCCAGAUGUUAGAGACAAAACUAAAAGUAAAAUACCAAGUGAAAUCAAAGCAUCACGAUUGAGCCCAGAACAUGAAAAAGAACUUCCUGGCCCACUUGAGAAACUGUUAAACCGGACAUACCUUUGGGGACUUCUUCCCUUCUCUGGAAUAAGAUUGAUGUUUCCAUGCUGUGAAAGACGAUGAUGUUCCUUCUCCCAGAUUCCUGCUGUCUUCAAAAGGCCUAGCAAAAACCACUGCUGCUGGGUGCAGUUGAGAAAGGGAAUGAAGAACAAUCCCAUGGCCAUGCAGGCACUCCUCCCCUCCACCUCUCUGCCCUCCACCCCUCUGCCCUCUCCUACCUUGUUCCUUCUUGGUCCUGCCAUGUUUGGACUGGUUCACCUUUUUGGCCCAUCACUUGGGCUCAUUCAGCAACAGUCAUGCCUUAGGUUGCAUCCUCAUCUAUAGGCCAAUUAAACAGGGUUUCUUCUUGAUAAAUCCCUAUGGUUUUGAUUUUAGGAAGUCAGGCAUGAUUUCUUUUGGGAUCUAUAUGACCCAAAGUGGCCAGUUUUACCAAAGGUGUCCCUUUGCACUGGGAUCUCUGGGUCUCAUUUGAACACAGCUUGGGUCCUCUUGCCUUGUCCCAGAGAAUCCCCAUGUUGUCAGGACAUAAGCAGAUACUCUAGGGCCUUCACCAAAAGCUACAAAGAAGCAGACAGGACUCAACUUAGGACAUCUUAUGGUUAUGUAACUAAGAGAUUAUUUUAGGAAGUAAACAGGCCUCUGUUGGCUCAAAUGAACAUCUUCAUUGUUAGUUUCCACUUACAUUGUUCUCGGGAUAAAUCGGCCAGAAUUUGGCAGGGCUCCCCAGCAGUCCUUGUGAAUCCCUGUGGUAGGAUGUUUCAGUUCUCCUGAGUCAGGCUGAAGUGAAAGCUCCUAAGAGAUAUUCAGAAAGAAGGAUGGUCAAGUUCUAGAACAACAAUAGUUGGCCCAGUAAUUUUAAAGAUUGUCAUUCUACCUAAGCCUUCAUCCUCCAGAUAGCACUGUUAUGGGCUUAAAAUAAGCUUCAAGGGAAAUAAUGAAUUUCUUUGACACCGCCAAAAAUCGGCUGUAUAUAAGAAUAACUUGAGAAUGGCUUACAAUGAGGUAGUCAAAAGCCCAGCUCAGUGCUCAGGAAUGUAUUUGUAAUUCCUCUUAGACUUGUCGAAUGGACUGCAAUUUGAUACCUAAGAGUAAUAAAAAAUGAGACCAUAUUUUAUGUUAAUGUUCCCUUCUCUUCCUCUGCCCACAAAAGUGAGGUCAGGGAAGGGGAGAGAAACUUAUCCUAAGCACUCCUUAUGAGUUGCUUGUGACAUGAUAGCUCUCUCUAAAGUUCAUGCAAUCCUCAUCGCAACCCCAUGAGGGAGAUGUUAUUGUCUCCAUCUUAUAGAUGAGGAAACUGAAGACAAGACCUUGUCAAAGGUCACACAUUGUAAGAAGUAGAGCUGCAUAUUCAACCAAAGCCCGUGUACCUGGAAAGCUCAUUCUCUCUCCCCCUUCUUCCUCUCAAAUCAGGCCCUAGCUCCUCCACAAUGCUUCGGGCUUCUACGUUCACUCAGCUUUACAGUAAAAUGAUCACAGACCCAUGAGUUCCCUGGAGAGUAGAGUGAUGCCUGGGUCAGCUGUUCCUCUUGUCUGUUCAGCAGGUCCUUUGAGUGGCUUCACAAUCCAGCUGUCAGUGGCAGAAAAUAAUGCCUCAUAAAUUAUUCACCUGGUUCACAUUGGAAUCCAUUAGCUCUCGGGGCUUGGUGUGGCUGCAGAUCAUCCACAAGUGCCCCUUGUUCUCUGCCCCCAAGGAGCUCCUGUCAUUGUUUUUAACCAAACAAGUUCAAAUAUCUCCACGUCUCUGCUGACUCUGGUCUUUUGUCUCUAGACUGUACCUUUAUUUCUGAGCUCUGAAAUUCUGCAGAAACAGGUGAGUCUAUAAAAACAUUCUGUGGGAGGCCAAAAGCUCAGAACAGUUGUGUCUCUCUUUCUCAGUAUUAAAAGAUCAAGGUUUCCCAUGGAAGCCAACCUGAUCUGGUAAUUGGGCCCUUCUAUACCCCUCUGAAUACUUUUCCAAGGAGGGGGCAGUUCCCACCCCCAUAGUUCCCCUGAGGGUUAAGAGUCCAGGUGGUGGCCAAGUUGCAAGAUUUGGGGCAGCCAUUUUGCCAAGGAUCAGAGAUUUGCUGUUGGAGAGGUGAAGUCGGCUCUGUGCCAUCCUGAAAAAUCAACUUAGAAAGAUAGGUGGACUUCAUCAGAUUUGUCAGUCCUUCCUUGUUUUAAAGAGAAAAAUGAUCUCUGCCUUGCUUCAGAUAGGAUAUGGCUAUUUUUUUUCCUUCUUUUUCUAAUGUAGCAGUGAUGGAAAACACCAGUCUUUGAAGAACAAAUGGAGGUUCCCAGUGACAUGAAUCCAUUAUAUUUGAUUUUGGAUUGUAUUUUUUAACCCCUUUUUAUGGCAUAGAAUUCUGGUGCCUUGCUCCCUGGGUUUGUCUCUGUGCUACGAGUAGGCUUUCUUCACAUUCUGGCUUACAGGGGAACACAACUAUUCCACAAGUGGCCUUUAGUGCUCUUUAUAAUAUGAUUUCCUGUAAUUUUUAAACUGUAUGUGUAAUUUAUAUUCUGGCUCUGUCCAAUAUUUGAACAACUUUAAUAGGUUGAUUUCCAUAUAUAUUAUGCAAAUAAUUCUUACCUGAUUUUUUAUGUUCUAUCUUAAAUAAAUACUGCACCACUUAUUAAUAAAUAGACAUUUCAGUGA